ACGGGGUCUGGCUCUGUCACCCAGGCUGGAGUGCAGUGGCACGAUUAUGGCUCAUUGCAGCCUCGACUUCUCGGGGCCAAGCGAUCCUCCUGCCUCAGCCUUCUGAGUAGCUGGGACCACAGGCGUGCACCACCAUGCCCACCUAAUUUUUUAUUUCUUGUAGAGAUGAGGUCUCCUGCCUCAGCCUCCCAAAGUGCUGGAAUUUACAGGAGUGUCGGCUGUGCCCCUUGUGAUGGGUGAGGAAAGGUAUCCACCUUUCUGAAUCAGACACAAGCUGCAGUAGCUUCCUGAUGCCUCAUUCACCAGGAUGGGUAACUUUAAAGACAAGUUUUAUAACUGGCAUCCCAUCUGGUUUCAGAGUCUUGGGGGCUUUUUUCAUACAGCUUUGUCUGAUAUUUAGAGACAUUCAGAUUCAGAAGCCAUGAGUUCAGUUAGCUCAUGGGCCGGGCACGUGCACUGACUCACUGGCUGCAGCAGAACACGUUGAGGGAGUCUUGGUGCACUUAGGUCACUGUAAGGUUCUAGGGCUGGGAGCUGGGAUUUGAACCAGGAUCUGUCAGCGCAGCCCCAGUGCUGUGCUUGAAGCCUCGUGCCACACUGGCUUUGAGGUAGCACGCUGCAAGUUAGUGAGUGGAGUUGCCCAAGUCUGGGGCUUCUGAAAUGACCUGGUAUUUUUAUGUUCCUGUUAGAAAUGGUGUGGCUUUCACAAAUUAAGUGCCAGGCUGGGCACAAUGGCUCGUGCUUGUAAUCCCAGCACUUUGGGAGGCGGAGGCAGGCGGGUUGCUUGAGCUCCGGAGCUUGAGACCAGCCUGAGCAACAUGGCGAAACCUCAUAUCUACAAAAAAUAAAAAAUUAACUGGUCAUGGUGGUGUGCACCUGUAGUCCCAGCUACUUGGGGAGCUGAGAUGGGAGGAUUGCUUGAGCCCAGGAGGUCAAGGCUGCAGUGAUCGUGCCAUUGCACCCCAGCUUGGGUGACAAAAUAAGAGCCUGUCUCAGAAAAAAAAAAAAAAACAAAAAAACCUAAUUGCCAGGACCCGCAAAUUCUGACUGAAAAAGACCUUCUUGUUCUCCCCACGGUCAUUCAUCUAAAUGGUUGUCAGUGGUACAGUGUUCAUCUUUUCUCAAAAAGUCAAGUUUUAUUUGAGGAAGUUACAGAUUUCCAUAUGAACUCCUAGAGAGAGAGCCUGCCCUUGUUCAGGGUUGCCCGGGGGAUGCCUGCCAUGUGGUAAGGUAAGGGUUUCUCUGCCCCUCAUCUCCCAGCCUGCUGUCCCCAGGAGCGAGUUCCUUAACCCCUAGCCGUGUCGUUGAGCCCAAGCUUGUAACCUGGAUAUGGGAGCUGUCUAUUUAGGAAGAAGGCAUGUGUGGUAAUUUCUAAAAGAAUUAAAAUAGAUUUUUAUGCUCUUGUAUUAUGUUUUGUGCUUAAAAGGAAGAGCCCCGAUAUAAUGGAGAAAAGCCAGAAGGAGCUUGGAUGCCCUCAGAGAGCCCUGUCACCUGUCUGUAGGGGCAGAAAGGAGGAUGCCUUUCCUCACCCAUCACAAGGGGCACAGCCAACACCUAGAAUAGAUUACCAAGGAAAAGUAUAAAAUGUAUGUAAAGACUUAGGUGACACAGGAGCCUUCAGAAAUAAAAACCCAAGAGAAACUGCAUGUUCACACUCAGAUUCAACGAAGAGUGGGUGGCUGUGCAGAAAUGUGAUUGGACAGAAGGGAAGGAUCUAAUCGUAGACUGGAUGGGGAAGCCUUGCCCCGUGUGUAGCUUUCUUCCUUCCAGGUACAGGGCAGGGCCCUUCUGGAAUGAAGGUCUGGGAUCCAUUUUCAGAUAAAGUAGUGUUGAGGAUGUCUUUGUGGCCGGCUCCUGUAGUGGACCUCAGAUCCGGGUGCUCGCCAGUUACAGAGUCCAGUUGACAAGAGCAAGGUCUGGUAGAAAGAAAGUGACUAUUAACCAGAACUAGUCAUGGGGAUAUGGCUGGAUUCCCACCCAAAGUAACUACUUUGAAUUCUGGAGAGAAGGCAAGGGUUUAAGAAGUGGGGAGUAGGAGCUUGAGCUGGGAGGCGCGCAGGGAUCGUGCUGAGUACAAUGUGUGUCUUGUUCCGGCGGCUGUCCUGGGCCUCCGUCCACCUGGAGUGCGGGCUGGUGUCAUCUCAACAAGUGGCCAGAUUUGACUGCUCACCUUGAGGUAAGCUCUGGGAUUUUGCAGCUGGGUUUCCACGCUUGGUCUGUCUCAAGAUUAGUCCCUAGAACUUCGAAGUAAGCACGUAAUUAGAGACUAGCUCACAGACACAUGUGAAGAGAGUAUACGGUGAGAAAGGGGAGGGGUAUGGAGUCUAUUUUAAGAUUAAGGGAAAAGGCUUCUGCAGUUUGCUCUAAGGUUGCAUCUCAGGACUAAAGAGAAAGGAAAAAAAAGUCUAAAAAUGCAUUUUGAAGUUAAGCUGCUCAGUUACACUCCUACACAAAGGCCAGGGAAAGUUAGAGUCAUAUUUCUAGUUUUUUUUUUUUUUUUUUUUGAGACAGAGUUUUGCUCUUGUCCCCCAGGCUGGAGUGCAGUGGCGCGAUCUCGGCUCACUGCAACCUCUGCCUCCUGGGUUCAAGCGAUUCUCCUGCCUCAGCCUCCACAGUAGCUGGGAUUACAGGCGUGUGCCACCAUGCCCGGCUAGUUUUUGUAUUUUUAGUAGAGACGGGGUUUCGGCAUGUUGGCCAGGUGGGUCUCAAACUCCUGACCUCAAGUGAUCCGCCUGCCUCAGCCUCCCAAGUGCUGGGAUUACAGGCGUGAGCCACAGAGCCUGGCCGUAUUUCUAGGUUUUAUGGCUGGCCUCGCAGGAGAGGGGUUCUGGUUUCUAUGACCUGCACUGGGGAAGAGGCAUUCUACUUUCCGUGGCCUACCUUGAGGGGUGGUGGGGUGCGGGCAAGGGAAGGGGCCAGAGGGUCAGAGAGCCCUUGCCUCUGAGGCCCUUCCGGUGUCCUGCAGUUCCUCAGUGUGCCAAAACCACAGGCCUUGGGGUAUCAUUUUCUGAGCCCCAGCAUAUCCCUCUAUUUUGCCCUUAGGUCUGGAGGAAGGUUCCAGGGCAUUUGCCCUUGGUGGGUGCAGGUAGGGAGGAUCUGCGGGUCUUCCUCAUGCCAGGAGUCUUAUCCCAGAAUCAAAGGCUCCUGGUGGGUAGGAGCGUGUCCCAUGUGCAGCACGCUUGGCUGUCCGAAGUUGCUGAUGAGAAGCAGCAUAGGAUCUGGCAGGGACGGUCCUGAGUGGAGAGGCUGAGAUGGGAGGUGGUGGCCCACGGUUAGCGGGCUGGAUUUUCUGGGGCAGCCUCCAUGCCAGCAUUUUGUCUUCAUCCCGGAACCCUGUGCACUGAGGUGCAGGAAGCGUGUGUAGUUUCACACACUUAAGUGUAAGAAAGCAUGUUCCUGUUGAAAAUAACACCCCGCUGGGCAUGCUGUGGGGUGACGGCAGGUUUUUGCCCUCCUCCUGCAGCUAAGCACUGGAGCCCUGGGUUCCCAUCGGGGCUGUGGCACUGUGCUGUUUCCCGGGCCACUGCCAGGGAAGGAGCCUCCUAUAUUGCUGGGCAGGGCCUGCGUGCAGGUCCAGGUUUAUAAAUUUUAGAGCUUGUUCAGAAAGCAGGCAAAAAGUGCUGUUGGAGGUGCUAAGAUAUAAAGGUUUUUCCCCGGGUGUGUAUUAUUUGCUACUUAAUAUUCUAAAGAAAAAUUAGAACAUUAAGUUAUUAACAUGAAUGUUUCUGCUUUUCUUUGCACUGUGUAGUGGCAAUUUCAAAUGCAAAUAUAAGAGCAUUUAACUUGUGUGUGGGAUACUUGAGCUGGCCCAUCUAUGUCUAUCUCAGCUUCUGCCAGGAUGCUGGAGGCACUGCACAAAAGGAAAUGCUCUUGAUCCAUGCACAUUCCCUCAGCGAAUGCUGCCUUAAGGCUAAGGUUACCAUGAGAGAGAAGGAGCUGUGGGUUGCCCUCUCAUUGCCUGCCUUCUGUGUCAUCUUCAGUGUGAGUAGUUGGCUAGUACAGGCAAGAGACAAGGCAGAGAGGAUAUGAUGGCUUCCUCCGUCAUCCGUGUUUCUUAGAAUGCAAUUGCUCUCUUUCUGGGCUGGAAGCAAGUUCUCAUGUGAUUGGAAAGCGUGGUGCCAGGGCUGUCAGCUCCAGCUGUCCUGUCGUAGCUGGUUACAUGCUGAUGUUGCCCUCGCCUUGAGUCUUGUCACCUCCGAUGCUGAGGCCCACUGGAACGCUGCUUCUGGCGCAUCGCGAACCCUGCAUGUUAGCCGGGUGGCAAGGAGUAGCCAGUUCUCUGCUCACCCACAUGCUCUGUGGUGCCCCUGCACUAACAGCACGAGUUCAGAUAAAAUUAUUAAGAAUUUCGAGAUGACGAAAGCAGAACGUGAAACUGAGUGUGGUCCUUCUGAGUGCAGGGCCCCAUGGGACCGCACAGGUGGCAGGCCUGGAAGGCCAGCCCUGCUUCAAGGAGUGUGGCUGAAGGAGGUCGGGGAACUCAGGCCCUGACCCCAGGGUUCUCCUUUCCCGGAGAUUCUGUUAAAGGGCCACUCACCUUAGCCAUGAUCUUCUUUGAACUUGCUCCGAACUGCUCGCUAGAGAAACACACACCCGGUCACCUGUGACCCCUUGUUCUAGGUGCAUUCCUGCAGGGACAUACUCUCCACCUGAUGCUGAAACCACCACAGCAAACAGGUGCUGUCAUGAAUAGUUGACAUGUAUUAAGUCAUUUAAUUCUCACCACAACCCUAUGAGGUAGGCAUCUUCAGCCCCAUUUGACAGAUGGGGAAACUGAGGCAUGGGUGAAGCACACUGCUCCUGGUCAUAGUACCUGUUGGACCUGGGAUUUGACUCUGGGCCUCCUGGCUGCAGUUUGCCCUCUUAACCCCUAUGAGGUGUGAGGAGUCAGUGAAUUGGCUCCUGUGGCUUGGGAGGGAGACAUGUUCCUCUGGGUGUCCAGGGACAGCACUGGGUGCAGGGUGGAGUGCUGGGCUGUGGAUGGGCCCAUAUUGGUCCUAAUGGUAGGCAGAGAGGGUGAGGAGGUGCCCAGGACCGGCUUUGCCAGAAGGAGAGAGAACGCUGGCACCACAGGAGCAGCCCACCGUGAAGGCCAUGCCCUGCCCGAAGCGCGGUGCCUAUUUAGAACCCGAGGGCCCCCCAGCACGAUGGCGUUUUGGGGGUUAUUUUUGUUGGUGGGGAAACAAGCUCAGGAAUUUGCCAAAGCUCUUAUCCAAGGGGCGAGUGGCUCAGCCAGGGUUCAUUACCAGGCUCCGGAUCCUGCUUCUCCCGGAUCACAGCAAGCGCUGUGCUUAGGCCUGGGGUGGGGGACGGAUUCUCCCUGAAGGCAGGUCUGACGCGGGCGGGAGCACCCACCCCGCUGGGUUCUUACGGCGGAUCCGUUACCUGGGUCUCCAGAGGGUGAGGUCGCCGUGGGCACCCUGGGAGCAGCAGUUCAGAUAGAAAUCCUCCCAUGCCGUGUGCAAACACUAAGUUUUUUGUUUUGUUUUGUUUUGUUUUUUUUGAGACAGAGUCUCGCUCUGUCGCCCAGGCUGGAGUGCAGUGGCGCGAUCUCGGCUUACCGGAAGCUCCGCCUCCCGGGUUCACGCCAUUCUCCUGCCUCAGCCUCCCGAGUAGCUGAGACUACAGGCGCCCGCCACCACGCCCGGCUAAUUUUUUGUAUUUUCAGUAGAGACCGGGUUUCACCCUGUUAGCCAGGAUGGUCUCGAUUUUCUGACCUCGAGAUCUGCCCGCCUCGGCCUCCCAAAGUGCUGGGAUUACAGGCGUGAGCCACCGCGUCCGGCCGCAAAUACUGGAAGUUUUAAGUCAAGCGAACAAACAUUAAACUGUUCUGUCCUCUUACCUUGACAAAUACACCUACCAGUGACCGGGAAGGCUGCCUUGUGAAUUUAGAAAGUCCUGGGUCUUGGCAGCUUCAGGGGACAGAUCGCCCCGCUCACGUUUGCCCCUCUUGCUUCCCACCCUGUUUCUGUCCCUUCCCCGGGGCCCUGGGGCACACAGGGGUGGGAUCGGGGGUCCAGGCCGGGAAGGGCUGCUCAGGCUCCGGGCACGCACUCCUGGGGGCGGCCUGUGCACAUCCCUUUUGGAGGGGUCUGCCCCACGCAUCCGGGGAGGUACGCAGCCCCUGGUGCCAGGGUCCAGGUGGUGCUACUGGGGAGGGCGCGUGCAGGAACCAGCAGCCCUGGAACCAGACGCCAGGGUAGGAGCUGGUCACGAGCCCUGCCUGGCUGGGUCGGGUCCCUGUCCUGGGUCCCAGAGUGCCCUGGACGUUGGGGCUGCAGGGACACCCCGGGGCCAGCGACGGCAGGUGAUGUCCAGGGCCCCGCGCCAACUGGGAGCUUUGCUGCCGCUGCGGCCUUGUGUGAAUUUGGAGGGACAAGGCCGGGGCGCGAACUGAAUCUACUGUCAUAUGCGGAGUCAAUGCACCAUCUCCAGGACCUCGAAAGCCUCAGUUUCCACGUAUGCAAAACGGUCCAUGGUGCCCUCGUACCCUGGUCGCUGCUGCACCAUCGAGGUCAGCGCGCGGCAAGUCCCAGGUAGGCCACGUCGGCUGCAGACCUCGGCGGCGGGCGGUGGCGGCGCGUGUCCACGCGAGGGCGCUGCGCACCGCGCUUCAGCCCGACCUCGCCUUCUGCAGGGGCGGUCUCCUGGCGCCAGGGGGCGUGCGAGGACCGAGGAGAGCGCAAGAGUAAGCCCGCGGGUGCCGGAGCGCGCGCCCCGCCGUGUGCUGGGUCCAGGGCGCGCGGCCGGCCUGUCCGGGCCUCCUUCGCAGACGAAGCGGCUGGAACGUCUCGGGGGCGCGCCAAGCCGGGGGCGCAUGCCUGCACACGUGUGCGGGGCUCACCUGGUGCUGCGGCCGGCUCGGGCGUUGCCUGCACGCACCGUGCUCUACCUGCGGGAGCGGAGUGGAGUCCGCGGUGCCUGCGUGGCCGGGGCAGGGCCCACAGGGUCCGGCUCAGAGCCCCGCCCCGCUGCCUGCGGCUGCCGAGCCUUUCCAAGCUCGAGGGGGCCGGGACCUUUGGGAAACCAGCGCCUGAGGCUUGGGGGCGGCCGUGCUGGGAGUGGCGGCUGCCGGGAAGCAGGGCGGAUCCCUGGACACCUGGAGCCCUGCCCCCUCGUCCCCGGGGACCCGGGGGUCUGUCUGGUUGGGGUCCGAGCGGCCUCAGGGUGGGCGCUGCAUCCUGGCCCGGGGUGCACGGUUGUGCGGGGGACACACUUGUCCCGUCCUGCCCGAGCUGCGACCUGGGCCAGAGAAGGGAGCGGAGCUGGCAUAGCCCCAGCCCCAGCUCACUGGGGCGCCUUGCCCGCCUCCCCAAGCCUGGGCCGGCUUGGCCGCUGCAGCCACCGGGCCUGGGCCCCAGCACUCGAGCCGCAGGGCGUCGCAGGCCUGGCCUCGCUUCCCCAGAGUCGGCCCUCCCCAGGAAUUUUUUGUUCCUUAGCCCUAGUGAACCUUCUGCGUCCCCUCGAAGAGGGGAGCCAAGGGACCUUGGGGACAGUUGAGGUUCGGGUUUUUAAAACACCAAUAGGCUUUAUUUUUAGAACAGUUCUACAUUUACAGAAAAAAUGAGCAGCUAGUCCGGAGUUCUUAUUACAACCCCUGCUGCCUCCCCCCGUGAACAUCUUGCACAGGCGACGUGCAUUUGUUCUAAUGAACGAACAAAUAGUGACACGUUACUAUUAGCUAGAGUCCAUACAGCUGAGGUCCCCUUUCUGUCCCAGGAUCCCACCGGGUCGCCGUCUGCUCACGCUCCUUGGCGGCAGCAUUUCUCAGACUCUCCUUGUCUCUGGUGAUCGUGACGGUGUGAGAGUAUUUUGAAGGCUCUUUCUCGACUGGGGUUUUCUCAUGGUCAGGUUGGGGCAGCGGUGUUUUGGGAGGAAGCCCGCAGAGGCAAGGCGCCGCCCCCCUCCCAUCACAUCGAGGCUACACGCUGCUGACACGCCUUCUGGCUGCGGCGCUGACCUUGGUCACCUCGCACGUCUCCACCCCAGUUCUGCUUUCUCCCUCCUUCUAUAGGGUGUCGUUGGAAGUCCCUGUGUGCAGCCUACGCUGAAUGAGUGUCCCUGAGGGGGAGGAGCCCAUAAAUUGCUGGGUUCUGCGUGGAGACUUCUGCAUAUUCAUCUCUUUUCUCCAUUUUUUUUUCUUUUGGAGACAGGGUCUCUCUCUGUCACCCAGGCUGGAGUGCAGUGGUGCGAACACAGCUCAUUACAGCCUCGACCUUCUGGGCUCAAGCGAUCCUCCCACCUCAGCCUCCCAAGUAGCUGGGACCACAGCCAUCAUCACACCUGGCUAAUUUCUUUGUAUUUUUUGUACAGACGGGGUUUUGCUAUGUUGCCCAGGCUGGUCUUGAACUCCUGAUCCUCCAACUUUGGCCUCACAAAAUGCUGGGAUUACAGACAUGAGCCACUGCACACAGCCUUCUCUGCAUUUACUCAUCUAUUUGAUCAUUCUGUCAGUGUAGACUCAUAGGUAUUAUAUAAGGGGUUAGGAGGGGUGUGGUUAUAGGCUGCUGGUGUACACUUGGGCACUUGUUGUGUGUGUCCCUAUGCUUGUCUGUGUUUGAAAUGUUUCUAAUGAAGUGAAAUAAAGAUGGGGUUAGGGCCGCCACUGAGGGGUGAACCAGGCUGGUAGACAGUCUCUUACCAGAGCCUGCCCCUGUGUCAGGGAGGGCUGGGUCUGGAUUGGGCUGUGUUGGGCCUUUGUCCCUGCCUGGUGCCCUGUCUGUGCUAAUGGCUAUGGUCCUAACAGAGGCUCCUGGGGCCUAGGGGGUGGUUCCUGUUGGCCUCUAAAACCCGCCCUACUCAGUGACCGAGAGAGCAAGUUGGGACCCACUGGGACCGGGCCCUGCCCUUCAGGUGGCCCUGUGGCCUCUCCGAGUGCAUGGCAGUAGAAGUGGUGGGGGACAUUGCAACCUGCAAAGUGCUGGGCUGGAGGCCACUUGCUGAGCCACGCUGUUUCUGGCAGGGACUUUCUGACAGGGCUGAUGUGUGUCCUGAAGGGACUCCUGCCUGCGUUUGGGGCUGUCCCUGAAGCGAGAGCACGGGGUGUCUGUGGGGGCUGGCUCCCCUCUCCUGAGCCCACCCCGGUCUCUGUGGAUGGCUGCCGGCCUGGGUUGAUGGAUGUGGGCUCAUUAUCUUGUCUGUCUUAGGGGAAGGUAUUAGCUUGGCAGUUCAUAAAAGAUUUUAAUUAAAGAGGGAAGAAUCAUUUUGGCAAACUAGCCUUGUUCCCACACUCAAAUGACCUGUCAAAGUUAUAAGUUCGGUUAAUUUCCACACAAAACCUUGCUAUUUUGGGGGAAUUCAGCUGGAGUCUGGGGCGACACAGCCCUGGGACUGGGCACCCUGGGUGGAAACCUGUUUCCCUCUCUCUUCUUGCCUGUGAAAGCCCCUGGCAGCCACCCUGUCCCUGCUUCUCCAAAGCCCCACUCUCUCUGCCCAUCUGCCCACAGUCCCCAUGGGUCCCAGUGUUACCCUUGACCCCUUUUCCACAUGCCCUUCCCGCCCAGGUCCUGGUCUCCUGCAGAGCUGCCUCAUCUCCAGGCAUCCACGUAGACUGUUACAUCCUCUUCUCCAUGUGCCAGUGAUGGGAUGCUUAAAAUACAUUUUGAGAGAGUUAUGGGCUCACAGGCAAUGGCGAGGGAUGGUACAGAGAGACCCUGUGUACCCUGCCCUGUUCCCCACAGCAGGAGAAUCUUGCAAAAUUGGAGUGCAGUAGCACAGCCGGGACAUCCCACCAAUACACCACGAGCCUUGUUCUGGCUUCAGUUUUUUGUGCACUGGUCUGUGUGUGUGGGCACGUUGAAUUCUAGACAAUUCCACCACAAGCACCCACAGCCAGAUGCAGAACAGCCAUCACCGAAGGCUCCCUCCUGCCCUUUCACCCACAGCCACCUUCCCUCCCACCCAGCUCUCCCGGGUCGGCGGGUGGGUCUUUUUAAACCACACCGCAGGUCACGCCUCCUGUAGCCUGCAGUGGCAUCUCCCAGGCCUUCCCAGGCCUUCCCAGGCUGGGUCCGCAGGACUCCUCACCAUGGCGGCAGAAGUGGCCCCUGAGUGACAGCAGGUGCACUUGCCCUGCCCGGCUGUCUCAGGACCUCCUCACCCCUGCCUGGAUGCUGCCUAGCCCACCCCUUCCACUGCCUCCCUCACACUCCUCCCCCUCCCCCGCCCGCCUUCCCCCUAUGCUCUCCCUCUGACUAAGGGAAGAGUUUCUCAGGAGCCUCGCUGCCCCUCUCUCUGUCUCUGUCUCUUUCUCUCUCUCAGUCUCUUUCUGUGUCUCUCUGUCUGUCUAUAUCUCUGCCUCAGUGUCUCUGUCUCUGUAUCACACUGUUUCUGUCUAUAUAUAUCUCUGCCUCACUAUCUCUCUGUCCCUUCAUGCUACUAGGACGUCUGGCUGCCCUUUCCUCCCUCCUGCAUCCCUGGCAUGUGGAACGGUGCUCGAUGACUCAGAUCCCUGCUCCCUACCUUGGUCUUUCCUGAGCGUGCUCAGGGCUGUGCUUGGGGACAGGAUGGGGACCUGUGGCUUCUCUCACCUCCUCUCCUGCCAAUGCCUGCUGCCCUGCAGGCCCCUGGAGGUCCCAGGCUGGUGACUGGGCAUGCAGACGAUGGAGGAGCCCCCAGGGGUCCUCGAGGCACCCCCUGGAAAGUGGCCAGGUGUUGAUUUGGGCCGAGCCGUGUGUGGGUCUCCUGUGGCCUGGCCACCAGCAGGGACAGAAAUGGCAGGGUGAUCACUGGCUGACCCAGAGAUUUUGUUUCCACUGAGCCUUGGCCUUCGUUGACUGUUACCACUGGGCUUUGAGUCAGACGUGGCAUGCUGCUAGAGAGCGAGAAAGAGCGAGAGUGAGAGAGAGAGAGGGAGGGGAGGGGAGGGGAAGGGAGAGGAGAGAAGGAGGGAGAGGGAGGAGGACGGGUGGUGGGGAGGAGGAGGUUCUGAAUUCUCCCAGACCUCCCGGCCGGCACCUCCAGGCCAAUGGAAUAUUUAGUUCUGAAUCCUUCCCUGGUGCAGAUUUCAAGUGAGGAGGGUGAUCUGGGCCUUGUCCAUCUCUGUCAUCUCUCAGGUGUCUGGCAGGCUCGGCCCCUGGCUCCUGGCCAUUGUGGGGGCACAGAAGGAGAAACAAGGACAUCCCUCGGCCUCAGGGGCUGGCUAGACACAGGCAGGAGUGAAGAUACACACGGCAUGGAAAGGCAGCCGUGGCCCUUAGCGACAGUGGCGCUGGGAGCCUGGCUCCCUGGGGGCGGUUCAGAGAUGAGCGAGAAGGAGCGGUGAGCUGGGAACGCAGUGCCCUCCAGGCCAGGGAGAGCUGGGGAUGGGGCUGUGGAGGGGCUCUGCUGGGGUCCCUGAGUCACACCGGCUCCUCUGUGGCACUCCUUGGCUUCAGCACCCCCUCCCCACUCCCUCCUGGGUGCAGGAUCCCCUCCUGCGGUGUCCCCUUGCUCCCCAGUGCUGGGUCCAUGGAGGCUGCAGACACCGUCUGCUUGUGCAUGUCCAACAUCCAUGCCGAGUCACUUGGUCACUCGGGGGACCCCACACAGCUGGCACCAGGGGCCUGCAGUGGAUGGAGGUCCAUCCAUAGUAAGUAUGGGGCUAGCCCUUGACCCCACAGUGACUGGGAGCCCCUCAGCUCCUGGGCAGGGUAGGGGUGAUGGAAGUGGAAAUGCUGCUGGAAAUACAUUGGCCUGGGCCGCUGCGGCAGGAGGAACUGUGCACGGCCGGAAACCCAGGUGCAGGCAGGCUAUGUGGGUGGUGGCUGCUGGCCUGGGGACAGAGGCUUCAAGGACUGCAGUCGUAGUGACACGACACUGACAUAGGUGGGACUGGCAGAAGAGGCCAGGUGGCCGGCUGGACCCGAGGGGUGGUCCUCGAAGCCAUUUUUGGCCCAGGGUGCCGCGGGCCAGUGCCAGGAGCCCCACAGGCAGCUGCGUCCUGUUUGCAUCAGAUCCGAAGGAUGGGAACAGGACAGGGAGCCAGGUUCCCAUCGCCCAUCAGGCCAGGCCUUCUCAGGAGCCCUCUGUGGCCUUCGUUAGGCUCCUAUUACAAGGCUGCAUAUGGACAGGUGGGGCUUACCUGAUUCUCGCAGCACAGAUUCUAUUUUUUGGAGCAGGGGAGCGGGCAGGCACCCUGCACAGCCCGGCCAUUUAGUAAGACUCGCUUCUUUCUGGGUGUGCUGGGCGUUCACUAUGCUUUCAUGUCAAUAGGAGAGUCACCGUCCCCACCCACUGUAUCACGCACCCAUUGCCACAGUAACAACAGUCAGAACCCCCACCCCAGUUCUCUGCUCCUGUCUGUUGCCAGCUGGGGCUUGUGGACUCUGCUUGGCGGGGCGCUCACACACGUGGGGUUGGCUGGGGGCUGGCUGCUCUGGGACAACCCCGGAUUGACAGCUCAGCUGGGCUCCACUGGGCCUCUCAUCCUCCCCACAGCUGGCCUGGGCUUGUCCUCAGGGAGCUCACAGAGUCCAAGAUGGCAAGUAGAUGUGUGUGAGCCCCUGGAGCCCAGACUGGAGCUAGUGCCAUGCCCAGUGUCCAGGGGUUGGGAGAGGCUUCACCUCUUCAUGGGGGCUGCAAAGGUGCAUUGUGGAAGUGUCAGGCUGCAGGGAGAGAAGACUGGUGUCCACUCACCUUACCAGCACAGUUAAGCUGCGGGGAGAUGACCGGCACUGGUGUGCAUGUGUGUGUGUGUGUGGGUGCCCAUGCAUGUGCAUGGGUGUGUAAACUCGUGGGUGCAUGGAUGUGUGUGCAUGCGCAUGGACACGUGCACAAGUGUGUUUAUACAUGUGUAUGUGUUUGUGCAUGUGUGCAUGCAUGUAUGUGGGAAGACGCAAGCUCAUUUCCAGUAUCCUGCUGGUGACCCCCAGGACAUCUUGUGGAGAGCCAGGAUCUGAGCCCAGAUGGGCGCCAGGGCAGGAGCUCUAAGCUUGGAGUCUCCAGCCUCCAACAGAGCGUGGACUGUCCCGGCUGCCUAGGAGAGACUCCAAGGAUGCUCACACAGCACCUCAGCUGCAGAAGGUUGCAGGGAGCAUGUUUGUGCAGCCUCUGCUCUGGAAUGGCUGUCCUCCACUACAGGAUCCUGUGGGCAUCCAUGGACACAGCAGGCCACAGUGUGGCACCAAGGCCUGAGCUCGCCUGCCACGGCCCGUGGUGGGCAUCCAGCCUGGCCCCUGCCACCCCAUGACCUGCGGGGCAUCCCUGCUCUCCUGGUAGCAGCAGUACAGUGUGGGCUGAGCACCAGUCAGGUCUGACAGGCUGCCCCUCUCCAGGUGGAGGGGGUAUUCCCUGUACCCCAUAUUCCCUGUCUGCCCCAAAUCCUCUGGGUCAGCGGGAAUCAGGGGUUUGAUGGAGCAUUCUUCUCUAGGCAGGGCCUCAUCGCAGUGUGAGCAGAGAGAAUCUUUCCUUUAUUAGGAUACAAACUGGGAGCUGAUUUCUUCUACUGCUUGUGGCUGAGUCCCUUGACGUAAAAAUUAUUCUGUUGAAGGGGGAUGAUGCUGCUACCAGCGUCAACACUGACAACCAUAACGGGGAAUGAUUUUCCAGCUCAAUUGAGUAGGUAUUCUGCAGAGUAGAAGCCACAGAGGAGCAUGGCCUGGUAGGGGCAUCACCUGGUGGAGGAGCAUCGCCCGGUGGAGGAACAUUGGCUGGUGAGGGAGCAUCAUCUGAGGGGGGAGCAGCACCUGGCAGGGGAGUAUCAUGUAGUGGAGGAGCAUCACCUGGUGGAGGAACAUCACCUGGGGGGGAGCAUAACCUGGCGGGGGAGCAUGACCUUGGGGGGAGCAUCACCUGGGGAGGGAGCAUGACCUUGGGGGGGUGAAUCACUUGGGAGGGGAGCAUAACCUUGGGGGGAGCAUCACCUGGCGGGGAGCAUCACCUGGGGGGGGAGCAUAACCUUGGGGGGAGCAUCACCUGGUAGGGAGCAUGGCCUAGUGGGGAGCAGCACCUGGGGGGAGCAUCACCUGGUAGGGAGCAUGGCCUAGUGGGGAGCAGCACCUGGGGGGAGCAGCACCUGCUAGGGGAGCCUCACCUGGUGGGGGAGCAUCAUGUGGUGGGGGAGCAUCACCUGGGGGGUAGCAUAACCUUGGGGGGAGCAUCGCCUGGGGGGGAGCAUCACCUGGUGGGGGAGCAUCACUUGGGGGGAGCAUCACUUGUGGGGGAGCAUCACCUGGGGGGUAGCAUAACCUUGGGGGGAGCAUCGCCUGGGGGGGAGCAUCACCUGGUGGAGGAGCAUCACCUGGGGGGAGCAUCACUUGUGGGGGAGCAUCGCCUGGGGGGUAGCAUAACCUUGGGGGGAGCAUCGCCUGGGGGGGAGCAUCACCUGGGGGGGGAGCAUCACCUGGGGGGGAGCAUCACCUGGGGGGGAGCAUCACUUGUGGGGGAGCAUCACCUGGGGGGGAGCAUCGCCUGGGGGGGAGCAUCACCUGGUGGAGGAGCAUCACCUGGGGGGAGCAUCACUUGUGGGGGAGCAUCACCUGGUGGGGAAGCAUCACCUGGUGGAGGAGCAUCAACUGGGGGGGAGCAUCACCUGGCCAAGGUGCCAGAUUCUGUGGCUGUCCUUUAAAUCCAAGUGUAGUGGCAUAUCCUUCCCCCUAAGCACAAAAGUCAACAACAUAGUGACAAGUUGCUCAUUAAGAAUUUUGUUGCAGGUUGGGCGUGGUCGCUCACACCUGUAAUCCCAGCACUUUGGAAGGUUGAGGUGGGCAGAUCACCUGAGGUCAGGAGUUCGAGACCAGCCUCGUCAACAUAGUGAAAAACUGUCUCUACUAAAGUACAAAAAUUAGCCAGGUGAGGUGGCAUGCGCCUGUAAUCCCAGCUACUUGGGAGGCUGAGGUAGGAGAAUCGCUUGAACCCAGGAGGUGGAGGUUGCAGUGAGCCGAGAUCACGCUACUGCACUCCAGCCUGGGCGACAGAGCAAGACUCUGUCUGGGAAAAAAAAAAAAAAAAAAGAAUUUUGCUGAGAACGUGUUUGGCUACCUGUGCGAAAAUGUGAGUAACUGAUUUCAAAUACAGCUAAAAAUACAAGUUGUAAAAAAGACACCAAAUUUUUGACCAGCAGAAUUUUUUUUUCCCUCAGGAGCUCUUGGAUCUCUUUGAGAAAUGUAUUCUGUUUCAUCCUUAAGCUACAGAUACGGAAAGAAAAUGUCAUCUAGAGGUUUCACAGCGCACCGGGAUUUAUUGUAGCAACGCCUUGCUUGCUAAAGAGGUGCUCAGUGAGAUGAUAUUCCAGUAAAAAGCCCACUAAGUCUCAGUGAAAUGUCUGAGUAGCAGAACGUUGAGGAAGCAAUUUGGUUUCAUUACUUGUAAGUGCACUGUGCAUUACAGAGUCGGGUAGGCAUGAGAAGCAUGGGGCAAGUUAAUGGAAAUAGCCUUUUACUAGAGGGACACAUUCCAUGAUGCUCUUUUCUUAAACAUACAUAUAAAAAUCUUAUCACUCCUAAAACAUCCUUUAGCUUUUAAUCAUGAGUUCCUAGAAGCCCAGGCUGCAACCAGGCACUGCUGCCCCAGGACCAGGUUCUGGGAUGAGUGUGACUGCACGGUCUCCAGGUGACCCUGGCCGGCCCCUUCCUCUCACCACUGAAGGCCCUCCUUCUCCUGAAAGACUGUAUCAAAAGCAGAUGGUGGGCUGGGUGCGGUGGCUCACACCUGUAAUCCCAGCACUUUGGGAGGCCGAGGCGGGUGGAU